CCCUUCGCUUUUUCUCAUCUUUCAAACGAGAGGCUAGGGGGUCUUUGCAGUUCCAGAAUGCUGUUGUGCCAUCCUACUGCGAGCUGAGAAAGAGCCCUAAAGUACGGUUCUGCAGGUACCGGAGAUGCAAAGCUUAACCAUGUUUAUUCUAGGAGGGGUUUCCAUUAAUUGGCUCCUAAAGUGGUAAGAAAUGUUAUCGUUGUCUGGAAGAUUAUGGAGCAAGCAGUCGGUGGUCCGGAGAAUGGCUUCUUAAGAUGCACAGGUUAAAACCUCUUUGGUGCCCUAAAGACAUGAACAAAAUCAGGAUUAAUGCUCCUAAGUUCUUCUUUCCUGUAGUUAAUCUAAUAGGAAACUUUGUAUUUGAACAGGUAAAAUCAAAACCCAAUCGUGGCAGGCAGCAGCAAAUUAACUGAACCCACCUUCUCUCCCGAGCACCAGAGCCUGAGUGAACAACUUGCCGCAGAAGAGCCUUCUCUAGUGUCCUCCACCGUCUCACCAGAGUAGGGAUGCUCUUCCGCUUCUCCUUAGUGCUGCCUCCAAACCAAUGCACCAUCACCAACCAAGUCUCCUCUCGGAAGAUGUGAAUUAUUAAAAAGAAAAUGGCCCAACGGAGCACUGUAUUUCCUUCUCGUGUCACCAAGGAAAGGCGAGUGAGAACCAUGCCCCGACACAGCCAGUCCCUGACCAUGGCACCAUACUCAUCUGUAAGCCUCGUGGAGCAGCUGGAAGACAGGAUCCUCUGCCAUGAGAAAACCACCGCCGCCCUCGUAGAGCACGCCUUUCGGAUUAAAGAUGACAUUGUCAACAGUUUGCAGAAAAUGCAAAACAAAGGGGGAGGUGACCGCUUGGCCAGGCUUUUCUUGGAGGAGCAUAUCAGAAACAUAACUGCCAUAGUGAAGCAACUUAAUCGGGAUAUCGAGGUACUCCAGGAGCAGAUUCGUGCCCGGGACAACAUUAGCUAUGGAACUAAUUCUGCCUUAAAGACCCUGGAGAUGCGCCAGCUCUCCGGUUUGGGAGAUCUUCGAGGAAGAGUGGCAAGAUGUGAUGCCAGCAUAGCUAGACUUUCUGCAGAGCACAAAACGACCUAUGAGGGGCUCCAGCACUUGAACAAAGAACAGCAGGCUGCCAAACUUAUCUUGGAAACGAAAAUCAAAGAUGCAGAGGGACAGAUUUCUCAGCUUUUGAACAGAGUGGACUUGUCAAUAUCAGAGCAGAGCACCAAACUGAAGAUGUCUCACAGAGACAGUAACCACCAGCUUCAGCUUUUGGACACUAAAUUUAAAGGUACAGUUGAGGAACUCAGUAACCAGAUAUUAUCUGCACGGAGUUGGUUGCAACAGGAACAAGAACGGAUAGAAAAAGAGCUUUUACAGAAAAUUGAUCAGCUUUCCUUGAUUGUUAAGGAAAACAGUGGAGCCAGUGAAAGGGAUAUGGAGAAGAAGCUCAGCCAGAUGUCAGCCAGGCUUGACAAAAUAGAAGAGGGUCAAAAGAAGACUUUUGAUGGUCAGAGAACAAGGCAAGAAGAGGAGAAGAUGCACGGGCGAAUCACCAAGCUGGAGUUACAGAUGAACCAGAACAUCAAGGAAAUGAAAGCAGAAGUUAAUGCUGGGUUUACAGCCGUCUAUGAAAGCAUAGGAUCCCUCAGGCAAGUUCUCGAGGCCAAGAUGAAGCUGGACAGGGACCAGCUACAGAAGCAAAUCCAGCUGAUGCAGAAGCCAGAGACCCCCAUGUGAAGGGAGCUGGGACAAGGUCCUAAAAGACAGUUUUGCCAGUGGGGCUAGGAGCCGGAUACCUCUGUAGCCAGGCCAUCGCUGCAUUCAGGAUUGUUCCAUCCAUGGCGUGCAUGUGCCAAGAAAUGUGUUUUUAUGGGUCUAAAUGUUUACCUUGAGUCUUGAAAAUACUCUUUUGUUAAAAGUAUGAAAUACAGUUUUUACCAGUUUAUUUCACUUCUCUAAAUUCAAUGGAAAUCCCCCGCCCUGGAUUUUGAAAGGCUUUUAUCUUCUUCAUUUUACGAAUGGAAAGACGACAAUUUUUCUUCAAUGCUUGAUGCACUAAUGAAGACUGUUUACUAUUUUGAAAAAUGUCAUGGGGAUUUUUUUUUAAUUAAGAAACUAAUGAAUCAUCACAGGAAUGUGUUGCUCCUCACCCUAAAUUAAGAGAAUGUCCCAGUAGAUUAGACUUCAACCUUUGAGUCCAAUUUGGAUUUUAUUAUCGUUGUCUAUGCACUUCUUAUAUUGGUUAUCUUCUUGUAAAUCUUCUGUCUUUUGUAAGGGGAAAGGAUUUAACAUUUAGAAUAAACCCCACCAUUUAUGUAAUGGAAAUAGUUUAAAAAUUGCUAACUGCCAUGUGGAUUGCAAAUUAAAUGGAAACUUAUUUAGAUAACGUAAGGCUCAAUAUCUGCGUUGACCACCUAGAUAUUACAGGUUUUAAUAUUUAAAACUAUUUUUGAAUUAUCCACAACCUGUAUAGUGAUAGCCAUAUAUUUAAUAAUGGAAUGGUGGUUAACAGUCUAUUUACUGCACAAUUAAUUGUUCACUAAUCAAAUAGAAUGUGGUAAUUUUUCAGACUUUAUGAUCUGUUUCCAAAAUUGGCACAAAGUGCUAGGGUUUAUAUACACUUAUCGUAACUGUAUUUUUGUGCCUUGGUUUUAUCAUGUCAAUGCACUGUACUCUGUAAAAGUUUUGCAGACAAAAUAGAAAGUAUGAUAAUCCGUCAGAAGUAUGAUGUAAAACUGGAAUCCUCUGUAUUUUUUAAAUGUUCUAAAAAUUUUAUCGCUGUUAAGGUAUUAAUCAUUCAGUAUUACUAAUGGAAUAGAAAUUCAUACUUUUGUAUGGACAACAAUUCAAAUUGAUAUUGCAUUUAUAGCACUGUAAGAAACUUUCAUCUUGAGCAACUUUGUAGAUGAUGGGUGUUUUAUUUUCAAUCGCCAUAUUUGAUCAGUCAUUGAAAAUUGGCCCCAGUGCUGUUUGUUCAUCUCUGUAUGUAAAAACUGACAGUGAGACACAACGUUCUGAACUGUGAGGGUGUCCCAGGAAAAAGAAAAACAGGAAUACUUUAACAAUUAAAAAGAAAAAAAUGUUUUUUGUUUGCCAAGGACUCAGGAAAAUAAAAAGCAUUUUCUAUUUUUAGGACAAAUCACAAAUGAAGUGUCUAACUGGCUAUUACUGUUUACCCAUAUAAAAUAUGCUGCUAAAGUACAUAUUUUGCUGUCAAUGGCUUGACAAUUUUUUUUUUCAAAUUUGGACAUGAGAGGUUAUAUAGGGACUAUAUUAUCCAACACAUAUUUUCUUAUUUUGCCACAAAUUUCCACUUAACAAAUAAAAAAAGGCGAAUGCUGUUUUGCAAUCAGAAAGUGAAUUUCUUUUGUGGUAGCGUACACGUGGUUCAUGUGGUUCUCCACGUUUAAGCACAAACCACAGCACAGGAAGCCACACCCCCUCCAGCAUCUCUGUCUUGUGGGGUCUUUGAGGAGAAGGAAUCAGAACAUCGACACCUGGGAAGAGGGAGGCGGGGAACACCAGCUGGACUCUGGCCAAGGAGUGAUGUAAGCAGGUGACACUUGGCUGUCAGCUGAGCUUCUCAGGUGCUUCUGACAUUGCCAGCCCCUUGAGAUGAGCCACCGCAGGUGUGCUCACCUUGGCUACAUGUUGAAAUCAUCCAGAGGAGUUGGGAAAUCUACUGAUGCCCCGCUGUGCCUCCCAGACCGAUUAAGUCAGAACCUCUGGGAGGUGGGUCGCAGGCAUCAGUGCGUGCCCGAGGCCUCCGCGUGUUUGGGUGUGCAGCCGAGGUGGUGAGCUGUCGAGCCACAGUGCAGUUCUCUUCUCACCAAAGCUCAAAUGAGAAUCAGCUUCCAUGUUCUUUCCUUUACCAGAAAUUUGCAAUAAAAAGAAAAAUAAAAUUUUCACAUAAA